AGUGGGUGCAGCCUGCUUGCGAGCUGAGGCCAGACAGGGGGGCGCCUACGGACGGAUAAGGAGGAGCAUUCCAGGCCGAGACGCCCUCAUCAGCAGAGUCACAGGAGUUUUGGAAGUGAGAGCAGGAUCAGCUCCUCCUCAUCUUCCUUCUCAGCAUACUCAUCAGGAAGACCGUGAGGAUGGAGACCAUGAUGAUCCACUUUCACUCAGUGAAUAAAAAGAAAAGUUGAUUACAAACGGGACCAUAUUUUGCUUCGAAAUGGAACCAGCAGUUAGCGAGCCAAUGAGAGACCAAGUCGCACGGACUCAUUUGACAGAGGACACUCCCAAAGUGAAUGCUGACAUAGAAAAGGUUAACCAGAAUCAGGCCAAGAGAUGCACAGUGAUCGGUGGCUCUGGAUUCCUGGGGCAGCACAUGGUGGAGCAGUUGCUGGCAAGAGGAUAUGCUGUCAAUGUAUUUGAUAUCCAGCAAGGGUUUGAUAAUCCCCAGGUGCGGUUCUUUCUGGGUGACCUCUGCAGCCGACAGGAUCUGUACCCAGCUCUGAAAGGUGUAAACACAGUUUUCCACUGUGCGUCACCCCCACCAUCCAGUAACAACAAGGAGCUCUUUUAUAGAGUGAAUUACAUUGGCACCAAGAAUGUCAUUGAAACUUGCAAAGAGGCUGGGGUUCAGAAACUCAUUUUAACCAGCAGUGCCAGUGUCAUCUUUGAGGGCGUCGAUAUCAAGAAUGGAACUGAAGACCUUCCCUAUGCCAUGAAACCCAUUGACUACUACACAGAGACUAAGAUCUUACAGGAGAGGGCAGUUCUGGGCGCCAACGAUCCUGAGAAGAAUUUCUUAACCACAGCCAUCCGCCCUCAUGGCAUUUUCGGCCCAAGGGACCCGCAGUUGGUACCCAUCCUCAUCGAGGCAGCCAGGAACGGCAAGAUGAAGUUCGUGAUUGGAAAUGGGAAGAACUUGGUGGACUUCACCUUUGUGGAGAACGUGGUCCAUGGACACAUCCUGGCGGCAGAGCAGCUCUCCCGAGACUCGACACUGGGUGGGAAGGCAUUUCACAUCACCAAUGAUGAGCCCAUCCCUUUCUGGACAUUCCUGUCUCGCAUCCUGACAGGCCUCAAUUAUGAGGCCCCCAAGUACCACAUCCCCUACUGGGUGGCCUACUACCUGGCCCUCCUGCUAUCCCUGCUGGUGAUGGUGAUCAGUCCUGUCAUCCAGCUGCAGCCCACCUUCACACCCAUGCGGGUCGCACUGGCUGGCACAUUCCACUACUACAGCUGCGAGAGAGCCAAAAAGGCCAUGGGCUACCAGCCACUAGUGACCAUGGAUGAUGCUAUGGAGAGGACCGUGCAGAGCUUUCGCCACCUGCGGAGGGUCAAGUGAGGGACACUGGAGGCUGGGCUCUCUCGACACGUUGCUCAGCCAGUCACUCCUUCCCCUGUGGAUUGAUGAAAUAACAUCCUUUGAAUGAGUUUGCUCUGAGCCUGUGACUCCUUCUGCUAGGCAGAGAGCGCACCCUACUCUUUCCGUGACGAUGAGGGCGGCAAAAACAGACAUUUCUUCCUUCAUGGAACUGGAUUUGGAUUUCUUGAAGCAGGCAGCUUCAUAUUAUACCGAUUUGUUCUCUGUCUUUUUGUGUCUCUCUGUUUACCCCCUCCCUUGCCCCCUCUUCUGGUUUAUACAUUUCAUUCCAGUGUCCUUGUACAUAAUCAAGGAAGCUGUAGGAAGCUACAACCCAUUUGUUAGUUCUGAUGGAGAACCAUUUCCAUGCAGACCAAUACUAGAGUGAAGCCUCUAGACUUUGUUCAAGAUACUCUAUCUUCAAAAUAUCCCAGAAGAAAAACAGAAGCUGUUAACACACAGGUGAGACUUUACAUAUACAUUUCAUACUGACAGUGAGCUUAGAGCAAAAGCUGAAAGCUGAAAUGACUGUAAUUCCUCCCCAGUCUCUGUUGCUUGUUCAACUCCUUACAUGUUCCACAUUCUCUUUCAGGUA